AGAUAGAACAAGAAGGCAGAAGAAAUGUGAAUUCCUCUUUCUCUGCUGGAGCUGGGAUAUUCUUCUUCUCCUGCCCUUGGACAUCAGAGCUGCAGGCUCUCUGGCCUUUGGACCCGAGGAUUUAUACCAAGCAGGUUUCUGGGUUCUCAGGCCUUUGGCCUUGGACUGAUAGUUACACCAUUGGCAUAUCUGGUUCUGAGGCUCUUGGUCUUGGACUGAGCCACACUCCUGGCAUCCCAGCGUCUCCAGCUUGCAUGGCCUGUCACGAGAACCCUGACUAAUACACCUGGAGUGCAGAAUCUGCUGGAGAAACUGCCAUUCCGUUAUUGACUGGCUGGUCAGGCCAUACAGCCUGGUGGUCUAGAUGUGUUUGGAGUGAUUCCUGUCAGAAUCACCAUUUUUGGUAAACAAACCAAGCCCAGAACCUGAUAAUUAUGGAGCAUUCUACACUGACAGUUCUUUGAGACAAAUUUCCUCUUGGCAUUUACACUGUGGCUUUAGCUUUCAAACCAGAGGUUCCUCUUACCCAGCAAAAAAUGGCUUUCCCGAAGAUGAGAUUGAUGUAUAUUUGCCUUCUGGUUCUGGGGGCUCUUUGUUUGUAUUUUAGCAUGUACAGUCUAAAUCCUUUCAAAGAACAGUCCUUUGUUUACAAGAAAGACGGGAACUUCCUUAAGCUCCCAGAUACAGACUGCAGGCAGACACCUCCCUUCCUCGUCCUGCUGGUGACCUCAUCCCACAAACAGUUGGCUGAGCGCAUGGCCAUCCGGCAGACGUGGGGGAAAGAGAGGAUGGUGAAGGGAAAGCAGCUGAAGACAUUCUUCCUCCUGGGGACCACCAGCAGUGCAGCGGAAACGAAAGAGGUGGACCAGGAGAGCCAGCGACACGGGGACAUUAUCCAGAAGGAUUUCCUAGACGUCUAUUACAAUCUGACCCUGAAGACCAUGAUGGGCAUAGAAUGGGUCCAUCGCUUUUGUCCUCAGGCGGCGUUUGUGAUGAAAACAGACUCAGACAUGUUCAUCAAUGUUGACUAUCUGACUGAACUGCUUCUGAAGAAAAACAGAACAACCAGGUUUUUCACUGGCUUCUUGAAACUCAAUGAGUUUCCCAUCAGGCAGCCAUUCAGCAAGUGGUUUGUCAGUAAAUCUGAAUAUCCGUGGGACAGGUACCCACCAUUCUGCUCCGGCACCGGCUACGUGUUUUCUGGCGACGUGGCGAGUCAGGUGUACAAUGUCUCCAAGAGCGUCCCAUACAUUAAACUGGAAGACGUGUUUGUGGGGCUCUGCCUCGAAAGGCUGAACAUCAGAUUGGAGGAGCUCCACUCCCAGCCGACCUUUUUUCCAGGGGGCUUACGCUUCUCCGUAUGCCUCUUCAGGAGGAUCGUGGCCUGCCACUUCAUCAAGCCUCGGACUCUCUUGGACUACUGGCAGGCUCUAGAGAAUUCCCGGGGGGAAGAUUGUCCGCCUGUCUGAGGGGAGCCCAGAGGCACAUCCGGACAAGUUUCAGAUAACCCGUGGGGAUAGUUUUUGCUAGAUUUUGGAAGAGGGGGCGGGACAGAGGAUGCUGUUCUUCAGUGCUGAAAUCCACGCCAGAAUGUCGGUGUUCAUGAAGUCACUGAUUAGUUCCCACUUGGUGCCCCAGGCAAUAAUAGGCCCGUCUCUUGGGCACGCACACUCUUCAUACUAAGUGUUUGACAUACACCUGGAUUUUUGCAUUUCAGGGGUCAGUAUCCUAUGACAUGAUGGGUGUUACCAUCCUAAUUUUACAGGCAAGGACACAGCAGCUGCGAGAGGUACAGAAACUUGUCCCAAGGCUCACAGCCAGUAGGCAUAGGAGCGGGAAUGAAAAUCGAGCACUGUCAGAAUCUGGUGGGCAGCCCCUGACUUGAACCACUCCCACGUGCUGCCUCCCUUAGGAGGGGACACUGAUGAUGAGGUCUCGGAGCCGGCAUCCUUCCAUCCCUGUCGAGUCCCCUCCACCUCAGCUCCCAGUCCUUGUGCUUUUUGGAGCUAAGCCUGGGAUGACCAAAUUCACCCCAGCUCCUUCAUUCACAGGGCUGGAUGUAGCUGGGAUUGAGUCCAUGUUAUCGGCUCGGUACUCAACACAACCCAAGUUUCAUCCGAGGAAAUGUCCCCGCAGUGGAUGCAGCUCACAUGCUGAGGAACACCCAGCUCUGGACAGAGUUCUUAUAAAUGUAUAAAUUAGGCUCAGAAACCACUGCAUUCUGACCUGCUGUACAGACUGCCCACACUGCUGACCUGCCUAGCGAGCAGGACAUCCCUUCUGAGCCAUCUGCUGCUCUCUCAUUUCAUCACCCCAACUGUCCCUUGUUUUUGAUCAAUGGGGACCAGCCACUGCCCCAGGAGCACUUUAGGGCUCUCAGUUCAAACUGAAGGACAGUUGAACUCAGAUGGGGUUCAUGUGGGAUUCUGGGAGCUUUCUGGGAAUUCAGUUGGAGUCAAGUCAGGAUGCUCUCAAGGACCCCUCGGGCUCAGAGCCCUAAAGUGGGCCCUGGUGAAGCAGGGUGGUCCUGCGUCCACUUCCCAAGCCUGAGCCAAGCUCAUCUUCAUUGAAUGUCUCAUUUGGCCGAGGAACAACUGAACUUUGUGGUUUGCUGUUUAGCCUUCAGUUUGCUCCGCUGCCUCCUACCCAGAGGUUUGUGCGAGCCUGUGUUGCAGGGUUGUAUAAAACCAAGGUACUUCGUUAGUUUUGCCCAUUCAGCCAUGGUCACGUGACAUGCAAAGUAAUCUUGCUCCUAAUUAUAGAAAUGAUUUUUCUUUUAAUUUUUUACUUUACCAGACUUUACUUUGUACUCAGAGAAGAGGCCUCACAUGGCUGUGUCACAUAUAAAUGUUGGACUAAACUCUUACUUGAACUCAGGAAAAGUUACUUGCUGCAAAAUGGUUUUGACCAUGUUCAAUUGCAAAAGUACGUCUGAUAUCCUAUUUUGCAUACCAUUUCUUGUGUUUGGAUUAAGCUGCUUCUUUGUAGAUGUGUUUCCUCAUCCUGGCUGCUCUGAACGCACUGGGUCAUGUUCAGAAAAGCCUCCUUCUCAGGUGGAAAAAAUCAGGGACUGAGCUUGUCUUUUGAAGCCCAAAUUUAAGAGCCACGCCUCUCGGUUCCAUAGGAUGGGCCGCCUCUCAUUCUGAAGAUGACUGUGCUUUGAGGGAGAAGUCGUCUGUUUGGCAGUAGGCCUGCGUCUGUGUUUCGUGGUCUACCUUGUCAGGUGUGUGUCUGUGUGGCCACUGGUCUCAGUCGGCGAGGCCGGUCCAGCUGCUGCCUCUGUGUGACUGGCUUUGGGUCUGGCCUUCACAGCAUCAGCUCACAGCCCACAGCUCCAGGGACAAAUGAGGACAGGCGUGGGCUCUCCCUACUGCUUCUGUGUGUUCUUAAAGGAUUUUCUUUGAGACCCAUUGUUUCCCCUCCCCUCCCCUCCCCUCCCAUCCCCUUCCCUCUUCUUUUCUUUUCUUUUUUUCUGACAGGGUCUCACCCUGUCACCCAAGCUGGAGCGUAGUGGCCUGAUCUCGCUGCAGCCUUGAACUCAACGAGCCUCAAACGAGCCUCCUGCCUCAGCCAGUGGGUAGUUGGGAUUACAGGUGUGUAUUUCUUUAUACAAUGAAUAAUUCUUUUUCUUGAGGAAAAAACAUUAUUUCAUGAAUCUAGAACUUGAAGGAACCUUAGAGCUCAUUCAAUCCUGCCUCCUCUUUUAUGUGGGAUGCAAACGAGGCUCAGAGAGACGUAACAACUUGCCCAGGACCUUCCCAGCUUGUUUGUUGCAGAAGGAGGGUUCCAGCUCAGCGUGGGUUUCCUGGUGCUGUCUUGUCUGGAUGUGAGAGUGAGAAACAAUGUGAAAGCAUGAGUGAGGAGGCCAAGCAGUGCUUCCCCAGGAACACCCAGCGCUAGCUCCAGAGUGGGAAUGGAGAGGUCCAGGUUGGCCGGGCCGGGGCUUCACCGCAGGCACCCAGAGAGGAAGGAUUCCGAUGGGCAGGUGCUGAGCUAGGGGCUGUGUAGGUAUUGCCUCAUCUACAUGCUCUCAAUGAGUUUUCCGGGGGCAGAGACCUGCAGUUGCUCAGGUUUACAGAUUAGGAAACUGAGGCAGAGAGAGAGAGGGUGAACAACUCAUUCAAGGUUACAUAGGUGAAAAGUGGUGGAAACGGGGUGACCCUAAGCUGCCCUGUGGCCUCCCCAGCCACCUGCUGACGGAGCUGUGGGAGCACAUUGCAUUGGCUGCUCCCACUGCCUCUCUGGGGUGCCUCCUCAGACUCCCCCAACCAUACACGCCUACACCCAGCCCCCAAACCUCCGUACUCUGCCUUCUACUGUGACUGUGGCAGAAGCCACUUGGCCCCCGUGGUGCCAGAACCCCUGGUAUUGGACUGACUCCAGCUCUUCUUCCACAGCUCCUGAUGUGGCCUCACUCUCGUCCUACCACCUGCUGUCCCCUCUGCUGGAUCACCCCAUUAGCACACAGACACGCUGCCAUUUUCCACCUGACCAGAAAUGGCCACCACCUUCCCCGACCCCUUCCCUGACCCCCUUCCCCGUCCCGCUGCCCCAUCCUGUUGCGUUUCUGGUGGAACCCCGCACGAGAGUUUUACUUGUCUGUUGCCUCGUCCUAAUCCUUCCCUUCUUUCCCAAAUGCCGUCUCAUCAGACUUCUGCACCCCCACUCCACCCACAUGGCCCUUCUCAGGGCACCCACCACCCCCUGUGGCUGGGUCCUGUGGGCAGUUCUUGUUCUCCUCCUGCUUGACGUGGCGAGUCCUCAUCACCAGCUUCCAGGACACCGGGUGCUCUUGGUCUCCCUCCUCCUUGCUGCUCGCCUUUUCCAUCUCCCCUGCUUGCUCCUUCUCUUUGCUCUGACAGUGUCGUGCUGGAGGAUCCUGGGCUCUGCGUGGGGCCCCCUUUCUUCCCUGGUUAUACCCAGUCCUCCGAGGGGCCCACCUUGUCUCAUGGCUUUAAAUAUGUUGAUGAUGUUUCCAUUUAUCUCCAGCCUAGAACUCUUUCUUGCUCUUCAAUCCACUGCCUACCUGAUUUCCCAUAGUGAACAAUCCAACACUGACCUUCUGGUUAACUGCCCCACAUCCAGCCCAUCUGCAGCCAUUCCCGUCUCAGGUAAUGGCCACUCCAUCUUCCUGCAGCUCAAGUGGGAAGCCCUGGAGCCAUUCCGACUCCUCUCCCAUCUGGUGCAUCAGGAAAGACUGUGGGAACUACCUUCAAAUUCUCUCCAGGAGCCAACCACCUCCUGCCCCUCCACUGCGACCACCCUUGUUCAAGCCUGCAUUGCCUCUCACCUGCAUUCGUGCAGCUACCUCCAGACCCUCCCUCAGCUUCCAUUAUUGCAUCCUUUGGUCUCUUCCCAGCAGCAUCCAGAGUGAUCCUUUGAAAAUCUCAUUUCUCUGCUCAAAACCCUCCUGAGGUUUCCCAUCACCAAGGAUAUUAAGGAUAAAAACCACAUCCUUCAUACCAUUGUCUACCUGUGAUUCCCUAAUCGUGUCCCUUUGCUCACUCCCUCUGGCCUCUUGCUGUUCCCUGAACAGCAGUCUGUUCCAGCCACAGCAGCCCCUUUGCCCUAUGUGCCCAUCCCCGUCAGCCUUGGCACUGGCUGUCCUCUCUGCUGGGAGUGCCCUUUCUUCAGAUGCUCUCAUGCUUCGCUUCUUUGCCUUGUUGACAUUUGGUCAAUGUCACCUUCUCAGUGAGGCCUACCCUGACCUCCCUGUAGGAAAAUGCAACUCACCUCACUCCCAUGCCCCGUACCUUAUAUUGUUUUCCUUGCACUUACCAAUUUCUAACAAAGCAUGUAAUAUCUGUUUAUUAUAACAUAUCUAUAUUUUAUGGUUUAUGUUUCACGCAACUUGAAUGUAACCUUUGUGUGGGCCGUGGGUCUUUCUCUGUUUCCUUCACUGACGCACCUUGGAUUCUUAGCAUGGUCCCAGCACAUAGUAGAUGCUCAAUAAACAUUUGUUGAGUGGAACUGAAUGUAUUGGUAUGGUAGGUGGGUUUUAGAAGGGAAUGGGUGAACCAGGACUGAAAAAAAAGAAAUAUUUUUCAAAGUAAGCCAACACUGUGGUUUCACUUGAGUCAGUAAGUAGGAAAUGGGUGCGACUCUGUGACCUGAAAACCUAGAAAUGCUCCACAGCCAUGCUCUUCACCCCUUUUCUUCCAAAACGGAAAACCUCACACAAUGCAGGGUGGACAGAAUCACACGGUGCAGUCUGUGCGCCUGUCCUCCAGCCCGACACCUGGCCAGUCCUGUCUCAUCUACACUGUCAUGCAAACUCUUGUUUUUGUUUGUUUGUUUUUGAGACAGAGUCUCACUCUGUCACCUAGGCUGAAGUGCAGUGGUGCAGUCUUGGAUCACUGCAACCUCCACCUCCUGGGUUCUUGUGCCUCAGCCUCCCGAGUAGCUAGGAUUAUAGGCAUGCACCACCAACCAGCUAAUUUUUGUAUUGUUAGUAGAGACGGGGUUUCACCAUGUUGGCCAGGCUGGUCUUGAGCUCCUGACCUCAGGUAAUCUACGUGCCUCAGCCUCCCAGAGUGCUGGGAUUAUAGGUGUGAGCCACCACACCCAGCCAUGUUUCAAGAAUUUGUGCUUCAGCUCAGCACUUAGUGGCAGUGGGAAGACCAGACCUCCUGACCCUUCAGCCUGCUGGCAUCCACCAUGCCUUAAAAAACAAAACAAAACCCUAAAUGUAUUUAAUUCCUGCUCCUCUUCAAACACACCAUUGUAACCACAUAAUACACUGUGUGAAAAGAGAGGAAAGAAAAAUCCAAGUCAACAAUAACUUGCCAGGCCUUCUUUCCUUGAGCCCCAUAUCCCACGCCCGCUGUGCUAACCUCUGGCUUGCCGCCCACACCUGUCUGGAUUCAUCCCGACUCGAGCCACCUCCUCCUAACUGGUCCCACGGGCCUGUCCCUGCCACUUUCCAAUCUGUCCUCCACUUGACAUUUGGAGUAAUUUUUUAAAACAGCAAAUCUGAUUAGGAAACUCAGAGGCCCAGGGAAGCCAGUGACUUGCCCUCUGGCACCCUGUCCUGAGGGUAGAGCUUCCUGGCACAGGGUCAGUGAGCCCCGAGGCCACCUCCCUGGAGGCUGCAGGAGGGUGAGCGUGGUCAAGAGCAGCAAUUUUCAUUGUUUCAUGUGUCAUUGCCUAUUUAACGAGCUUCGCAGUGCCCUCAAUUUGCUAAGUUAACUUUGGCCACGCCGUCCGUGAGAGGUCAGACUGGUGAUUUCCAACUCCCGCCGGGCACCGGGUGCUGCACCGGUUAUCCCAACAGGCUGGCACAGAGGGCUGAAAUGGACUUGGAAAGCCAAAUAAUUAAUUUUCAUGCGAGUUUUUGAUCCCCUUGAGUGUGGUUAUUUUUGUGCAAAAAAUUAUCCCGAUGUUUACUUUGGUUUCAUAAGUAAUUUAUUAAAAUUCCUUCCUAAGCUUUAAAUUUCAGCUAACAAAUAUGAGCAUGGCCUCUGGGAAUGGUAAGAACAAGGAAGCAUUGUGUGUGUGUGUGCACACCCCAAGGUUGUGCAGCUAGAAGUGCAGAAUGUGGAUUCCGUCCGCUCUUUAGGGCACAGCUAGCCCUGUGCACCUGUAGAAACUGUACUGACGUACAGCCUUGCAGAGCCUCCAGCUUCCAUGGUGGCAGGAGCCAUGGAAAAUAGAGACCCACCCGGUAAGGAGGUAACUGGGACACCAGGUUACUGUCUACCUGGUGGGGAAGCUGGGGAAAAGGGCCCAUGGGAGGAUACUAACUGGGGAAGAGGAGACCUUGCUUCCAGGGCUGGGCGACCCACUUACGGAGGCCCCAUUCCAUUUACAUCUCCGCUCAAGCCUCCGCCUCCGGGUUCCAGCCCUGGCUCUGCAAUUUGCUAGCUGUGGCCCCAGGUGGUCAUUCUCUCUGCACCUCAGUCUCUGCAUCUCUAUAAAAUGGGAUGAUAAUAGUGUUCACCUCAGAAGGUUGUCAGAGGUGUGGAAAUUAAGAUAAUUCACAUUGAGUUCUUGGCACGGCUGUGCCUAGCACUGGGUGCAGGCUGAAUGCAUGGGCUGCUAUCGCGAUGUUGUAUCUAAUGGCCUGCAGUGGUUGCUUAGCAGCAAUGGGUUUGCUUGGUUAUUUCCUGAUUUGGGGUAAAUAGAUCCAGAGACCAAGGCUCCAUGUUAUCCCCAGCACCGGGCUGACCCCAAGUACCAGAGAGGUCUCCAUGGCCCCAGGCUGCAGAGGACCCAGGUUACAACUUGCUCAAGUAGACCCAGGAUCUAGGCUUAUCCUAGUAGAUCUUGGUACCAGGCCAGCCUCUGUGACCUGAGACUCCAAGACCACCAUUGCAGACCCAGGCUCUAAGCUAGCCUCUGCAAACUCAGGAUAUAUAUUCCAAAUAUCCCUGAUUUGGGGGGCAAGGUCUGUGUGUGAUUUGCAGAGUAACGAUAUGAAGAAGGAGGUCUUGUUAAGAUGGCGUGGUGUGGAGUGCCCAGGUGUGAAAUGGUUGUCUCAAUGGAAGUUGUAGCCUCCUCCUCCCAUGACAUCAUCCUCACACGUGCUCAGUGUUAGGCAUUUUUUCCCCCUCCUGCUCUGAAUCAAUGCGAGUGAGAUAUGCAUGCGGGAGGGACAAGCUUGCAUGGCACCCAGCUGUGGUACAUUUAGAACUCGGCCUCAGCCCUCCAGUGUGACCUUGGGCAUACCCUUCACCCCCGGGCUCUGUUCGCUGGGGCAGGGUCUGCGCUCUGGAGUCAGGCUGCCUGGGUUUGAAUUUUACCUUCCUCGCCAAGUCCCUUGAGUGGCAAGUUACUUAUCUUCUCAUUGUCUCCGUUUUGUUAUCUGAAGAAUGGGACCAUAGUAGUUCCCGCCUCAUGGGAUGAUCAUGUGGGUUAAAUGAGAGGAUGAGUAUAAACUGCUCAACAUCCCAUGGUAGGUGCUCAGUAAAUGCAGGUGCUUAUGAUUAUAGUCAGUGUUUGGGCUGUGAAUUUUGGUGGAUUCUAUGGUGGUGUAUACAGCACUAUCUAUCAGUGUACCUGUCAGUGUCUGGUGAUCUCUGUGCAAAUCAAAAACUCUUCAGAUUGAGUCUGUAGGGCUUUGUUUCAGCUCUUGUUCUUUUUCUUCAUUUGAAUCUUUCCUGGAACUCUUGGAGAAGUUCUUCUGUUCGUGACAUUCUUCACAAUCAGAGCACUGUGUUCUUGACCCUCUUAAUUCAGAAUAUGUGAAAAUCUGAAUGAGGUAAAAGAAGUUGGAGCUGGAAGAUGCCUUAGAAAUUAUCUACAGUAUUUUUUUUUUUAAGAUAAAACCUUUUACAGUUAGGAAAGCCAAAGCUCAGAAAAAUGGAGUGACUUUGCCAGGUCCUUCAGCGAGUGGCACAUCCAGGAUUAAAAGCUGGCAUCAGAAAUCCCAUGUCAGACAUUCAUUCGUUUAUUUAUUCAUCUGUUGAGUGCUCAGUGCUUUGACCGGGCAUCCUGAAUGAGGGUCAAGCUGAGGUUCGAGGCCGUGGGUUUUGCAUACAGAGCUUUCACUGGGUAAAUACACAAUGCUGAGAAGAUUAUCAGGGGCACCUGAUCCCUUGACAGCUGAAUAAAGAAGCGUUCCAGUGCCUUCUCUGUGGGCAUCGUAAGCCAUGUCCAUCCAUACCUGCUGUUUCACUGAAACCCCACAGCAGCCUCUGGAGGGCACCAUUCUUAUAAUUAUGCCCCUGGAUUUAAGAGGAGGAAACUGAGGGGCAGGUGACUCAGUGACUUCCCCGGGGGCUCAGACGUGGUGGAGACACAGGCCCUCGGCCUCCAAAUGCUGCCUCCCGCGAGCAGCCUUGCUUUUCUCCACUUGGCACAGUGGUGAGUCCUCCGAUGUAUCUGCUUUCAUAGGAAGCUUGGGACCAGCCCUGCCCAAGGAGUGUGCCACCUGACCCCUUUUCCUGUCUUCUGUCACUUUUUUUUUUCCAAGUGUUGAUAUGAGUUUCAGUCUGCCCCUUCCUGGGCCUGUUUGACCUCCUGGGAUUCGGCACUUAGUUAUCUGUGUCAUUCCCAAGGACCUCCCGUUUAGCUGGAUCCCCUGACCUGUCCUGCCCUGGCCAGCCCUCUCUUGAGGUUACUCAAGUGUCCAAUGGCAGCCCAAACAAAUGUCUGGCUUCAGAAAAUAAACUCUUCAGUCCAGCCCACUUUCCCUGUCUCCCUAUCUAAUGCCCUUGCAAAACAAGCCCGGGGGCGCCACACUCAGACUGUGUGUGUGUGUGUGUGUGUGUGUAUCUAUGAGAGAGAGAGAGACAGACAGACAGAUCUGAGGCUCUAAUUAGAGAUACCAUGCUCAGUGGAAGCUGGUUCUGAACAAUGUUAACUGCCCCACCCGUGUCCAUGAAGGGCAGUGGAAGAGCAAGGGGCGGUUUAAUUACCUGGGAUGUAAAACAGCAGGCACCCCCACUGCCCUCCUCAGCUGUUGGGGUGGCAGGGUGGAGUUGAGGGCCUCACUCGUUUUCACCUUUGCACAAUCAGUCACACAUUUGUUAUAUGACAGCUAUGUGCCACACACCCAUGUUCAGUAAGGUGGAAGCCAGCUGCAGGCGUGGUCCACAGUUCCAGACAUCUCUGAAGGAUGUGACACCAACUUUCAGGCAGAACAUUUAGAAAGAGUGAAAUAAAGUGAAACAGAUCAACCAGCCUAUUGAGUAUCUACGUGUUUUUUUUACAGGCAAGAACUGAGGAGGCAAUACUAUUUAGAAUCCUUGAUAAACAGUUCCAAAAGAAAAAAAAAAACAGGCUUUGGUGACUCUCAUGGGCCCUCCGUGCCAAGAGUCUAUGGCUCUGUGAUAUAUUAAAUCAGGCUUGUUAAUUAUUUAAUCUAACAGCUGCCAUGCACCCUCAUUUUAAAAACAGAUGAGGCAAUGUUUACAUUUUCUCCAUGUCCUCCAUUUGGAAGUGUCUUAGUUUGUUUUGUGUUGCUGUAACAGAAUACCACAGACUGGGCGAUUUAUAGACAAUAGAAAUUAAUCUGGCUCAUGGUUCUAGAGGCUAGGAAGUCCAAGAGCUUGGCACUGGCCUCUGGUGAGGGCCUUCAUGCUGUGUCAUUGUGGGCAAAAGAGCAAAACUUGCUUUGAUAAAAUCACUCUUGGCAAUAACUGACCCUCCUCUUAUAAUAACAUUAAUUCAUUCAUGACAGCAGAACCCUCCUGACCCAGUCACCUCUUAAAAGGUCCCACCUCUCAACGCUGUUGCACUGGGGAUUAAGUUUCCUUACACAUGCACUUUGGGGGACACAUUCAAACUGUAGCAGGAAUUAUUUGCUUUCUCAUAACAUUUUUUUAAUUAAUUAAUUUUCAGCGUUUGUUAUAUCAGAAUGGACAUUAUAGCAAUUUCCAUGGCUGUGUCGCUCCUGGCAGAUUUUAAAGUUCUUCCAGCCUGAUUCCUCUCUCUGUUUGGGUCUCUGGCAUGGUGCCUGCUGGAGAGUAGAUACUUGAUAAUUAUCUAUUGGGUUCUCAGGGGAUCUCUCAAAGGUGGUAUUCAGGCACCCACAAGGCAACUCCCAUCACAAGAAAGAAUGGUGGCCUGGGAGUGAGCUGUAAGGUUCCUUCAAACAUCAGUUCCUGAAGCCUCUUUUAUUCAUUAUUGUUGGGACUUGUUUUUAUUUCUGUUUCGUUCUACGUGACCCCAAAAUCUGUAUGUGAACACUAGGAACUUUAUCAUGGGCUGAGGUGUAUUUGAAGUAAACUCUUAACUAUGUCUCUGGGAUAUGAAAGGUGCUUACAUUCUCUGUUGGGAAUGUAGAGAGAAGGAUUUGCAGUGUGUGGCCCCUGGGAAUGUAGAGGCAUGAAUUUCUGUCUGUUUUCCUGCUGUUGAAAUCUGAGUGCUAGGAACGGACCUCUUGCUCUCAGAUUGGCCUUGAAGCUGAAGGGAACCUGUCCACCCUCUGCACAGGGCAAGAGCCACGCCAACAGGAGGAAGUUGGAGUGCAUCCUGGCACCUGCCAAUCGGAAGACUGACAAACAAAAAAUUAGUUUUUAAUUAAUUUAAAAAAUGAUCUUCCUACUUAUCAGACACAAUCACUUUUAAAUAUGAGCAGAAAAACGAACUCCAUAGCCAAAUGCAACAUUUUGUGUCAUACUGCUUUACAUCAUCUAUUCUACCUCCAUUCACUGGUCAAAGAAGCGCAGAGUUAAGUUGGCCAGUGUGGCGUGGACACAGCCAGGCGCAGACCCUCCUGCCAGCGAAGCCAGCGUGAGGUCUGUUGGCUCAGGGGUCCAGUCCCUGGGUCCCCGAAGAGGUAAGCCAAAGACAUAGUGAUACUUGGUUCAAUUCGGCUCCAGAGAGUAUCAGAUGGGAAAUAGAUGACUUGUUUUACCUGGUCAAAUAAGACAUCACUAAAAUCUACCAUGACUGGAAAUUACUUAAUGCAACCAGAGGAGACUUCGCAGUCAAAUUUUGCUUUUCCUAAAAGACACGAAAUUAAAUUUACAUGUCACUGAAUGCUAUUUGAAACUGUCAUUUCCUUGUAUAUUAGGGGGAUCUGCUAGACUCUUAUGUCAUUGUAUUUUGGAAAUGGGUAUAUGUCCUUAUUAUUGGUUAAUAAUCAUAUUUAUUUUUAAUGAAAAUUAAAUUAUGAAAAUAAUGCACUUAACUAGGUGAGUUUUAGGUUGUCGAUUGAUGUGAUAAUUCACUCUUCCCGAAAAAUUGGCAAGGUAAUGGUCUGAAUCGGACAAUCCUUUUGUUUUUACAUUGAUGUUUUCUAUAUUUAUUUUGUACCUGGAAAAAUAUUUUUACAAUUUAUUUUGAUUUUAUAUGUGUAGAAAAAUGUACUGAACAAUGUUGACAUGCUUAUUUUUGUAAGAGAUGGGUACUUCUUGUUCCCCUUGGAUUUCGGAAGCAAAGCAAUGGGACCCUACGCUUCAGAGUCUUAAUGGGGUGGGGCAGUGUCCAUUGAGGUGUCCUGUCGGGAAUGACAAGUCCAGGGCAGAUUAUGAGGCAGGCAUCCUUUGGAGUUCUUCUCUCAGGUAUAUUUUAACUAAAAGCUAUCAUUUAAGUUGAAGAAAUCAAGUCUUGUGAAUUGAUACGAUUGUACUUCUAGAGUCUUUGAUGAUAAGUUGUCUUUGCGGUACAGAUUGGCUCCUCGAUCUUUCAAAGUGUCAUUUAAAUGGAAAUAAAUGUCUGAAACAGA